GCGUGCGCGUGCGCAGGGAUAAGAGAGCGGUCUGGACAGCGCGUGGCCGGCGCCGCUGUGGGGACAGCAUGAGCGGCGGUUGGAUGGCGCAGGUUGGAGCGUGGCGAACAGGGGCUCUGGGCCUGGCGCUGCUGCUGCUGCUCGGCCUCGGACUAGGCCUGGAGGCCGCCGCGAGCCCGCUUUCCACCCCGACCUCUGCCCAGGCCGCAGGCCCCAGCUCAGGCUCGUGCCCACCCACCAAGUUCCAGUGCCGCACCAGUGGCUUAUGCGUGCCCCUCACCUGGCGCUGCGACAGGGACUUGGACUGCAGCGAUGGCAGCGAUGAGGAGGAGUGCAGGAUUGAGCCAUGUACCCAGAAAGGGCAAUGCCCACCGCCCCCUGGCCUCCCCUGCCCCUGCACCGGCGUCAGUGACUGCUCUGGGGGAACUGACAAGAAACUGCGCAACUGCAGCCGCCUGGCCUGCCUAGCAGGCGAGCUCCGUUGCACGCUGAGCGAUGACUGCAUUCCACUCACGUGGCGCUGCGACGGCCACCCAGACUGUCCCGACUCCAGCGACGAGCUCGGCUGUGGAACCAAUGAGAUCCUCCCGGAAGGGGAUGCCACAACCAUGGGGCCCCCUGUGACCCUGGAGAGUGUCACCUCUCUCAGGAAUGCCACAACCAUGGGGCCCCCUGUGACCCUGGAGAGUGUCCCCUCUGUCGGGAAUGCCACAUCCUCCUCUGCCGGAGACCAGUCUGGAAGCCCAACUGCCUAUGGGGUUAUUGCAGCUGCUGCGGUGCUCAGUGCAAGCCUGGUCACCGCCACCCUCCUCCUUUUGUCCUGGCUCCGAGCCCAGGAGCGCCUCCGCCCACUGGGGUUACUGGUGGCCAUGAAGGAGUCCCUGCUGCUGUCAGAACAGAAGACCUCGCUGCCCUGAGGACAAGCACUUGCCACCACCGUCACUCAGCCCUGGGCGUAGCCGGACAGGAGGAGAGCAGUGAUGCGGAUGGGUACCCGGGCACACCAGCCCUCAGAGACCUGAGCUCUUCUGGCCACGUGGAACCUCGAACCCGAGCUCCUGCAGAAGUGGCCCUGGAGAUUGAGGGUCCCUGGACACUCCCUAUGGAGAUCCGGGGAGCUAGGAUGGGGAACCUGCCACAGCCAGAACUGAGGGGCUGGCCCCAGGCAGCUCCCAGGGGGUAGAACGGCCCUGUGCUUAAGACACUCCUGCUGCCCCGUCUGAGGGUGGCAAUUAAAGUUGCUUCACAUCCUC